GAGCCGAGCGCCGCGUCUCGGGAGUUGAUGGCAGCACCACUGUGCGGCCGCCCGGCCGAGCGCGGAGCGCAGCCACUCGCCGCUGCCCAGGGAGCGCCCAAGAUGUGGGGGGACCGGGGCGGCAGCGGCCGUAGCAGCGCCAGGGACGGGGGCACGCAGCAGCCUCCGCUCGCCCGCCUGUCCUGACCUGCCUCGCUUGCCCCCAAAGAAUGUCAGCCAAGUCCAAGGGGAACCCCUCCUCGUCCUGUCCAGCCGAGGGACCGCCGGCAGCCUCCAAAACCAAGGUGAAGGAACAGAUCAAGAUCAUCGUGGAGGAUUUGGAAUUAGUCCUGGGCGACCUGAAGGACGUGGCCAAGGAACUUAAGGAGGUGGUUGACCAGAUUGACACCCUGACCUCUGACCUACAGCUGGAGGAUGAGAUGACUGACAGCUCCAAAACGGACACGCUGAAUAGUAGCUCAAGUGGCACAACAGCCUCCAGCCUAGAGAAGAUCAAAGUGCAGGCUAAUGCACCGCUUAUUAAACCCCCAGCACACCCGUCUGCUAUCCUCACGGUCCUGAGAAAGCCAAACCCUCCACCACCUCCUCCAAGGUUGACACCUGUGAAGUGUGAAGACCCCAAAAGGGUGGUUCCAACUGCCAAUCCUGUAAAAACCAAUGGCACCCUUCUACGAAAUGGAGGCUUACCAGGUGGACCUAACAAAAUUCCAAAUGGAGAUAUCUGCUGCAUACCCAACAGUAACUUGGACAAGGCUCCAGUCCAGCUUCUGAUGCAUAGACCUGAAAAAGACAGAUGUCCCCAGGCAGGGCCUCGAGAACGAGUUCGGUUUAAUGAAAAAGUACAGUACCAUGGCUAUUGUCCUGACUGUGAUACCCGGUAUAACAUAAAAAACAGGGAGGUCCACUUACACAGUGAACCUGUCCACCCACCGGGAAAGAUUCCUCACCAAGGCCCUCCCCUCCCUCCUACACCCCAUCUCCCUCCUUUCCCACUAGAAAAUGGGGGAAUGGGAAUAAGCCACAGUAACAGCUUCCCCCCUAUCAGACCUGCAACUGUGCCUCCUCCCACUGCACCAAAACCACAGAAGACGAUCUUGAGGAAGUCAACCACUACAACCGUGUGAUGUAUGCCAUUAAAAAAAUUGUUUUUUUAAUUUUCUAUAUUAUAAACAUAAAAUAAGUAAUGAGCACUUUCUACUCAAGCAAUAAAAAGCCCAAAUAUAUUAAUCCUGCAUUCAGCAAAGUGGCAUAAAAAUCACCUGCUCCUUCAGGUUGGAAGGAAUACCUUUACUUGGGGGCAUGUCAAUUCGUUUUUCUCACUUGAUUCAUCUUUAUGACUUCCUGAGGACAGAUCUAAUUCUAAAGUAACCAGAAGCCUGGCCAUCUCAGAGCAGCAAAUCCCUCAACCUUGGAGCACAAAUGAUCGCUGAUAGAGUCUGCAUAAAAUCAUCUUCCUCUAUCUGACAGCCAUGAGCAGAGCCUUGGGGGUAAAAAAAGCCACAGCCUUAAAUCUCUUCACUCAGAAAUUACCAUGAAGAUAAAAUAAAUAAAUGGAAAGGACUAUCAAGAAGCCAACAAAACAUAAACACCAAACCAACUCAUCUUGUUUCACUUUGGAAAUAAACUGUUCCCAGAUGUGAGACCAACAAAAUUAAUAUUAAGCAAUUAAACCAGUAAAUUAUAAACUGAUUUAUCAUUUGGGAAGUUUAAAGUACAGAGAGAUGAGGUACCUGUAGCCAGAAUUACACAUCAUUUCAAAAUAUGUAGACAAAAAGAAAACUGAAUGAACAGAGAAACAUUGCAGCAAUGCACAGUCUUAGGACGAAUGUUGCUGUUUGCAGACAGAGAAUGUUUGCCAUCUUGUGUAUAGCCUCAAAGCCAUACUGAGAUAAUAGCAUUGUUGUCAAUUGCUUGAAAAAUUUUCACAUUCAAUCCUUCAUGCUAUAUUGGUUGGAAGAGGAGGGAAGUCAGUUCUUACUGAUUACUUCUCAGUGAACUUCUAAUAUUUGCACUGUCACUUCCAUUCAGGGUAAUGAUGUGUGCUGUUAUUUGCACAGAUGGUCCCAUGAGUUUUGAGACCACAGCAAGCAGUUUUUUGCAGGAAUCCAAAAUGGAAAAAUGUAAGAAUUCUCAAGACAUUGAUUUUUCUUCUUUCAAAAAAAAAAAAUCAGUUAUCUAAUAAAAAAUGGAUUUGAUUUUAAAACAAAUUUAAAAACAUCUACAGAAUAACAAUGAAAAAGCAUCAGUGUGGUCAAAUGAAUCCAAAAGGGAUCCAAAGUUUUUAAUGACCAUCAUUUGAUAUCAUUAAAAACCAAGAAGUCAAAUACAGUGAAAUGCACACUAAGCAUUUGUGUUGAACAUCUAUUUGUUCUCUUAAUUAAAAAGUCAUUUGUAAUUUGUAUUUGGCAUAUAACAGUUUUUAUAGCCAAACAGCAUUUUCAGUUUAUUUUUCUAAAUAAAUCUGUUGUUUGUAUUGUUUGUAGUUGCUUAUUUGAUUUGGUUUUCAUUACCAAGAAAACAAGUUUCUUUUGGUUUAUUGGCAAGCUUUUGUCAUAUUAAUUCAGAACUAAUGGAAGAUUGAUAUUUCAAGUAUUUUUGUAGUAUAAAAUUGUGCUUUCUGUUUUCUAAGCUCUGAAAAACAUGGUAUAUUUUUCACUAUGACUUUCUUGUGAAGGGCUAUUUUAACAUUAUAGUUAUAACUAUUGAGAAUUAAUUUUAAUACAAGGGAACAUUGCUAGAAAACAGAAAGCUCAGGUAUUGUAUCAGUAAGGAUUUUUUCUAAGUUUUGUUUCUGGAAUUCUGUUUAGAACAUAAUAAUUAGAUUAAAAAAAAAGGUCACUAAUCCUAAGUGUUCUCAUUAUUGUUAUCCAGAAGUCUGCUAAGAACUUCUAUCAUCUAUCUAUCUAUCUAUCUAUCUAUCUAUCUAUCUAUCCAUCCAUCUAUCAUCUAUCUAUCUAUCUAUCUAUCAUCUAUCUAUCAUCUACCUAUGAGUAGGUAAUCAUACUGGAGCAAAAAUGGAACUCAAUCAAAAAGGGCUGUUUGUAGUGUACAAUUCAAACAAAUUGCUUAUAACAAUUAAAAGAAUAGGUCAUUAGGCUUAUUCCCAAACUAUGAUAUAAAAUCAAACUCCCAACAUGUUGUUCUGUACACUUAAAUUGGUUUACACUCUGCAAUAUCUCCUGGUACUUAGAAUACCUUGCAAUGUAAUGAAGAAAAUUAGUUUGUUUUGCAUGAUUUGAACCUCUGAAAAGUAAUAUAUUGUACAUUAAAAUAAUCAAGCAAGGAAUCAAAUUGCCAGUUCCUGUGAGAUGAUAGGCAUUGAAGUAUAGAUGCCUGAACUCAUCCAUGAAGCAAUCCAUGCUGAUUGCUUCAAUCUGUAAAUUAUUUGAACUUAUAAAUAGGAAAGCCAACUUUCCCAAAAAUAUUUGACAAUAAAAUUAAUCAAGCAUAUGUGAUAAAAAAUAUAGUUCUUUAUUUUGUGCAUAUACUCAGUGAUAAGCAGCACUUUACCAGCUGUACUCUCUCACGAAUGUCUAAAAGACUGCAAAUAUGUGAAAUGAUCAGGCCUGCUCUUCAGCAGGAUAACUCCAGUAGUAGUUUAUAAAGUGAGUUAGAGACUGGAGGUGGCCAGACUAGAAAAAGUGUCUAAAAUUUUCUUUGAAUUUAGUCUGUUUUUUCUCUUAAGUUUUGAUUAUAUUUACUUUCUUAGUUAUUUCACUUGUCCAUCACUGUUUCUUCUUUCAUCUUCAACUUUUAAACCUGCUAUUCUCACAAGUCAGUAUUACUUUUACAAAUCUAUUAAACAAUUGCCAGUUCCCACUGAGAAGUACUACUUAACAGGUUUCAUUUUUAUCUCGAAAUGCCAAUGUAGAUAAUCUUCACUUCUUAACAUUUUCUUUUAGAGUGCUGGUGUCUUACACAUAACAUGCAAGUCUCUCCUUGCUGGCCCCUAUUCACAUAAUUAUUAUGUUUACUUAGGUAAGAUAAUCUUGCUUAUUUACUGAGUGCUCACUAUGGGACAUGAAUUAUGCAGGUCAUUAGGAACAAAAGGGUAAGAAAAAAUACAUAGACUAUUUUAAUAGAGUCUAAAAUCUAGUUGGAGAGAACUACAUUAAACAUUUAAUUACACGUUAACAAAAAAAUUACAAUAUGCUAAAUUCUAUAAAGAAAAGGAUGUGGGCUGGGCGUGGUGGCUCACGCCUGUUAAUCCAGAACUUCGAGAGGCCGAGGCCAGGGGGAUCACUUGAGCUUAGGAGUUCGAGACCAACCUGGACAACAUGGUGAAAUCCUGUCUCUACAAAAAAUAAAAAAUUAGGUGGCUACGGUGGUGGGUGCCUGUAGUUCCAGCUACUUGGUUAGCUGAGGUGGGAGGAUGGCUUGAGCCCAGGAGAAGGAGUUUGCAGCGAACCAAGAUUGUGCCACUGCACUCCAGCCCAGAUGACAGAGCAAGACCUUCAGAAGUUGUGUAUCUAAACAUACCUAAACAUAUAAAAGACACAGUGACAAUAUGGUAUAACCUUGUGGGACCACCAUUGUAUAAUAUACGUAGUUCCUUGUUAAUGGAAUGUGGUUAUGUGCUGAAUGUAUCCAGUACAACAAAUGUAGGCAUGUUUAACUCCUGAAAAGAUUAAGACCCUGCCUCAGAAAAAAAUAAAAUAAAAAGAAAAAAAAAGGUAUAUGGUUUGGAGAUAUCACAUGUCCAGUGGCUCUAACCCAGUGGGUAGAGAAAGCUUUGAACUGAGAUCUGAAGGGUGACUAGUGGAUAAAAAGGGAAAAAUCAUGUGCAAAGCACUGCAAAGAGGAAGAAGGUAAGACAUCAGAAGACCUGAAAAAAUCUAGAGUUGUGCAAAGAGAAAAAAGAGAGUAGUGCAGAGAAGACUGGUUAGAUGGAAAUCAGAUCUCACCUAUCUACAUCCUAGGUAAAGAAACAAAAAUAUGAAGAGUAAAAACAAUAUAAAGAAUAAAACAGUACGAAGAGUAAAACAAUAAGAAGGGUAAAAACAGUUAAGUAUGCAGAAAUGACAGAAGUAUAGUCAUGUAUUGCUUAAAAACAGGGAUACUUUCUGAAAAAUGAGGAGUUAGGUGAUUUCAUUAUUGUUCUAACAUCAUAUAAUGUACUUACAUGAACCUAGAUGCUAUAGCCUAUUUUGCUUGCAGGGCACAAACCUGUACAACAAAUUACUGUAUUGAAUACUGUAAGCAGUGGUAACACAAUGAUAAUUGUGAAUCUAAACAUACCUAAACAUAGAAAAGAUACAUUGAAAAUGUGGUAUUACCUUGUGGGACCACCAUUGUAUAAUAUACGUGGUUCCUUGUUAAUAGAAUGUGGUUAUGUGCUGAAUGUAUCCAGUACAACAAAUGUAGGUAUGUUUAACUCCUGAAAAGACUAAGAUGACAUUUUCCUCCCACCACCAAGUCCACUAUAAUCUCUCUCACUCAUCAACAGGAAAGAUUUACUUGCACUGCCAAAACAAAGAGAUGCAGAAAGUUACAUAUUUGAAACAAUAGGUUAAAAUAUAUCUGACUGAGUAUAAACUAUAAGAAAAAGAGGCUCAAAAUGAAUACAAUCAUGACUCAUAUUAUUGUGCUUUGCUUUGUUGUGCUUCAGACAGAUGUUGUGGUUUUUACAAAUUGAAGGUUUGUGGCCUAUAUGGGGCAAGUCUAUCAGCAUCAUGUUCCAACAGCAUGCAUUUACUUUGUGUCUCUAUGUCAUGUUUUGGUAAUUCUUACGCUAUUUCAAGCAUAUGCAUCAUUAGUAUAUUGAUAUUCAUAUUAUUAUAUGUGUUAUGGUAAUAUGUGAUUUUUGAUGUUACUGUUGUAAUUGUUUUUGGGUGCCAAGGAUGACGCCCAUAUAAGAUGGCGAACUUAAUCAAUAAAUGUGUGUGUUUUGACUGUUUCAUCAA